GGUUUUGCGGCGGCACCGGGAGGGGUAAGGGAGGUGAGGGCGGCGGGUGCCGAAGCGACGGCAGCGGCCGCGGCCGGAGGAGCAAUAGCAGCAGCCGUGGCGGCCACGGGGCGGGGCGCGGCGGUCGGUGACCGCGGCCGGGGCUGCAGGCGGCGGAGCGGCUGGGUCGCCCAUAUUUGAUUUUGAGCUCCAAAAUGGAAGAUUGGAAAAUAUGUUUUGAAGAGGUGUUUCAAAUUAAAACAAUAAAGAGUUUAUGUGUGGAUGAAUGGAAGGGCCUUGACCGCUUUCUUUGGCUUUGGGAAUGUACAAAAUACCUCAAAUGUUAAUAUCCUACCAAAAUUCCCAAGAUAAGUAAAUUGUGGUGUAUCUAUAUGAUAGAUUACUAUCAAGUCAUCAAACAUCAUGAGGAAGAAUGUUGACUUGGAAGAACCUUCACUAAAACACAGGCUGUAGAAUAAUAUAUGUGGUUUGUUAACAUUUUGGUAAAAAAUAAUAGGUAACUAAGGCAUAAAUACCAAAAACCGAAUGACAACGUUAAGAGUGGUUUUUUUCUUGGAAGUAGGUUUAUAGGUGUUUUUUUUCCUUUGAGUCCUGUUUUCCAAGAUUUUGUUUUAAACAUGUAUUGUAUUGCUAAAUAUUACUAGAAAUAUAGGAGAGGGCUAAAGUUCAUAAACGGUCGAAAUACACUGUUUGUCUAUAGUAAGUCGAUAUUCUCCCAGUUGCACAUUAUUAAGUAUUCUUAACUGUCCACUAUAAAUUAUUGAUUGUUAGACUUUUGAACUUGUAACUGUAAUCAAGGCCAUUUUAAAACUUGGCAUUGAACUCUGGAAUCUGUCUUUCCUCUUCAUGGAAAGACAAAAUUGCUGAAGGGAUGCUUACAGGCAUUUUUUUUUUUUUUUUUUUUUUUUUUUUGAGACAAGGUCUGACUUUGUUGCCCAGGCUGGAGUUCAGUAAAGUGAUCAUGGCUCACUGAAGCCUUGUGCUCCUAGGCUCAAGCAGUCCUCUCACCUCAGCAUCCCAAGUAGCUGGGAUUACUGAUGUGCAGCACCACACCCAGCUAAUUUUAAUUUUUGUAGAGAAAAGAUCAAUCUAUGUUAUCCAGUCUGGUCUUGAACUCUCUGCCUCAAGCGGUCAUCCUGCCUCAGCCUCUCCAAGUGCUGGGACUACAGAUAUGAGCCCCUGUGCCUGGCUGAGGACUUUUAAACUAUACAAAUAAACUUUUUUUUUUGAAGGUCUCAAGUGCACUUUUUUUUUGUUUUUUUUGGAGACAGUCUUACUCUGUCCCCCAGCCUGGAGUGCAGUGGCGCAAUCCCAGCUCACUGCAAUCUCUGCCUCUCUGGUUCAAGCAAUUCUCGUGCCUCACCCUCUCGAGUGCCUGGGAUUACAGGUGCAUGCCACCACCUUGCCUAGAUAAUUUUUUGUAUUUUUGAUAGAGACGGGGUUUCACCGUGUUGGCCAGGCUGGUCUUGAACUCCUGACCUCAGGUGAUCUGCCCACCUCAGCCUCCUAAAUUGCUGGGAUUACAGGCAUGAGCCACUGUGCCUGGCCCUAAGUGCACUUUUAAUACAUUUAUUAAAAGAUAAACUGAGCACAUAACCUAUACCAAAUACUAUCCUGUAAGACAGGUCUACAAAAAUGAAUAUGCUGUUCCUGUGCCUGGGGAACAUGCAGAAGUGAUUUCACUUUAUGUUGUUUUUUUUUUUUUCUUGAGACGGUCUCGCUCUGUCACCCAGACUGGAGUGCAGUGGUAUGAUCUCGGCUUGCUGCAACCUCUGCCUCCUGGGUUCAAGCAAUUCUCAUGCUUCAGCCUCCCAAGUAACUGGGUUUACAGGCAUGCACUGCCUCAGCCAGCUAAUUUUUUUUUUUAUUAUUUUUUUGAGACAGAGUCUUGCUCUGACGUCCAGGGUGGAGUGCAGUGGUGCCAUCUCGGCUCACUGCAACCUCCGCCUCCCGGGUUCAAGCGAUUCUCCUGCCUCAGUCUCCCAAGUAGCUGGGAUUACAGGUGCGUGCCACCAAGCCCAGCCAAUUUUUUUUGUAUUUUUAGUGGAGACGGGGUUUCACCGUGUUAGCCAGGAUGGUCUUGAUCUCCUGACCUCAGGUGAUCCAUCCGCCUUAGCCUCCCAAAGCGCUGGGAUUACAGACAUGAGCCACCGCACCCAGCUAAAUUUUUGUAUUUUUCUUUAGUAGAGACAGGGUUUCACCACGUUGGCCAGUCUGGUCUCGAACUCCAAGUGAUGCACUGGCCUCGGCCUUCCAAAGUGCUGGGAUUACAGGCAUGACCCACCACUCCCGGCAUUACGUUCUUAUUUUAGAGAUGAAACAGAUCUGAGAGGUUACAUCAACUAAUCAGACAACAUCAAGCUGAUAAUCAGAGGUGGAAGACUUAGGACUCCUAUUCUGGUCUUAGGAGCAAAGGUCCUGUUGUUUCUCCCACCUUAUAACAUUGCCCUUCUUGUCAGACUUUCAAAAUACAUUUUAAAAUGUGUCCCAUGGAUAAGAAAAUACUUGAAAAUUAUCCUUAAGUUGAAACUUUUUCUUAUCUUACCAAAGUAAAUUAAUGAUUCAAGGAUAUUGGGAUAUUGUGUCAUCCGAACGACAUACACAUGCUGAUAAUGUAUUUUUUUGUCAUUUGAUUUUCAGUGGAUUAUUUAUAAAAGUAAUUUUGAACUCCUGCCAAAAUGGUUGGCCCUUUUUUUUUUUUUUUUAACCUUGUCAAAUUUUUAUAUGGUGUCUCCAAUGCAGAUAGGACUUUUGGAAAUAAAUGUUCUUUCUCUGAAUUUUUUUUUUGUGGGGGAGGGUGUUUUCCAGACCUUUUGCUCACAUGAGCCAUUCUUGGUUUGUUCCAGCUUGCCAACACUUGGUGUCACAUGUGAGCCUCCCACAUGUAUUCACUCUCCAUUCCAGCUCUGUGAUUGAACUCUGCUCUUAUUGACUAGGGGGCAGUUGGGCAGGCAUGCCUCAUUCCUGGAAUUGACAGUCAUUCCUAAUUUUUGAAUAUACUAACACUGAAUCAGCACUUCUAAAGCCCUUCCUUCUCCCACUGGCUUCACUUGGCUUUCAGACAUAAUGAGGAGACUGGCUUUUCGAGGCGCUGGUUGUGCUCUGGUAAAGCUGAAGAAGUUGGAUUCCAUGGGUUCCAAGAGAAGAAGAGCUACCUCCCCUUCCAGCAGUGUCAGCGGGGACUUUGAUGAUGGGCACCAUUCUGUGUCAACACCAGGCCCAAGCAGGAAAAGGAGGAGACUUUCCAAUCUUCCAACUGUAGAUCCUAUUGCCGUGUGCCAUGAACUCUAUAAUACCAUCCGAGACUAUAAGGAUGAACAGGGCAGACUUCUCUGUGAGCUCUUCAUUAGGGCACCAAAGCGAAGAAAUCAACCAGACUAUUAUGAAGUGGUUUCUCAGCCCAUUGACUUGAUGAAAAUCCAACAGAAACUAAAAAUGGAAGAGUAUGAUGAUGUUAAUUUGCUGACUGCUGACUUCCAGCUUCUUUUUAACAAUGCAAAGUCCUAUUAUAAGCCAGAUUCUCCUGAAUAUAAAGCCGCUUGCAAACUCUGGGAUUUGUACCUUCGAACAAGAAAUGAGUUUGUUCAGAAAGGAGAAGCAGAUGACGAAGAUGAUGAUGAAGAUGGGCAAGACAAUCAGGGCACAGUGACUGAAGGAAAAGUACUUUUUUCUCCACAUUACCAGUCUUCUCCAGCUUACUUGAAGGAGAUCCUGGAGCAGCUUCUUGAAGCCAUAGUUGUAGCUACAAAUCCAUCAGGACGUCUCAUUAGCGAACUUUUUCAGAAACUGCCUUCUAAAGUGCAAUAUCCAGAUUAUUAUGCAAUAAUUAAGGAGCCUAUAGAUCUCAAGACCAUUGCCCAGAGGAUACAGAAUGGAAGCUACAAAAGUAUUCAUGCAAUGGCCAAAGAUAUAGAUCUCCUCGCAAAAAAUGCCAAAACUUAUAAUGAGCCUGGCUCUCAAGUAUUCAAGGAUGCAAAUUCAAUUAAAAAAAUAUUUUAUAUGAAAAAGGCUGAAAUUGAACAUCAUGAAAUGGCUAAGUCAAGUCUUCGAAUGAGGACUCCAUCCAACUUGGCUGCAGCCAGACUGACAGGUCCUUCACACAGUAAAGGCAGCCUUGGUGAAGAGAGAAAUCCCACUAGCAAGUAUUACCGUAAUAAAAGAGCAGUACAAGGAGGUCGUUUAUCAGCAAUUACAAUGGCACUUCAAUAUGGCUCAGAAAGUGAAGAAGAUGCUGCUUUAGCUGCUGCACGCUAUGAAGAGGGAGAGUCAGAAGCAGAAAGCAUCACUUCCUUUAUGGAUGUUUCAAAUCCUUUUUAUCAGCUUUAUGACACAGUUAGGAGUUGUCGGAAUAACCAAGGGCAGCUAAUAGCUGAACCUUUUUACCAUUUGCCUUCAAAGAAAAAAUACCCUGAUUAUUACCAGCAAAUUAAAAUGCCCAUAUCACUACAACAGAUCCGAACAAAACUGAAGAAUCAAGAAUAUGAAACUUUAGAUCAUUUGGAGUGUGAUCUGAAUUUAAUGUUUGAAAAUGCCAAACGCUAUAAUGUGCCCAAUUCAGCCAUCUACAAGCGAGUUCUAAAAUUGCAGCAAGUUAUGCAGGCAAAGAAGAAAGAGCUUGCCAGGAGAGACGAUAUCGAGGACGGAGACAGCAUGAUCUCUUCAGCCACCUCUGAUACUGGUAGUGCCAAAAGAAAAAGGAACACUCAUGACAGUGAGAUGUUGGGUCUCAGGAGGCUAUCCAGUAAAAAGAACAUAAGAAAGCAGCGAAUGAAAAUCUUAUUCAAUGUUGUUCUUGAAGCUCGAGAGCCAGGUUCAGGCAGAAGACUUUGUGACCUAUUUAUGGUUAAACCAUCCAAAAAGGACUAUCCUGAUUAUUAUAAAAUCAUCUUGGAGCCAAUGGACUUGAAAAUAAUUGAGCAUAACAUCCGCAAUGACAAAUAUGCUGGUGAAGAGGGAAUGAUAGAAGACAUGAAGCUGAUGUUCCGGAAUGCCAGGCACUAUAAUGAGGAGGGCUCCCAGGUUUAUAAUGAUGCACAUAUCCUGGAGAAGUUACUCAAGGAGAAAAGGAAAGAGCUGGGCCCACUGCCUGAUGAUGAUGACAUGGCUUCUCCCAAACUCAAGCUGAGUAGGAAGAGUGGCAUUUCUCCUAAAAAAUCAAAAUACAUGACUCCAAUGCAGCAGAAACUAAAUGAGGUCUAUGAAGCUGUAAAGAACUAUACUGAUAAGAGGGGUCGCCGCCUCAGUGCCAUAUUUCUGAGGCUUCCCUCUAGAUCUGAGUUGCCUGACUACUAUCUGACUAUUAAAAAGCCCAUGGACAUGGAAAAAAUUCGAAGUCACAUGAUGGCCAACAAGUACCAAGAUAUUGACUCUAUGGUUGAGGACUUUGUCAUGAUGUUUAAUAAUGCCUGUACAUACAAUGAGCCGGAGUCUUUGAUCUACAAAGAUGCUCUUGUUCUACACAAAGUCCUGCUUGAAACACGCAGAGACCUGGAGGGAGAUGAGGACUCUCAUGUCCCAAAUGUGACUUUGCUGAUUCAAGAGCUUAUCCACAAUCUUUUUGUGUCAGUCAUGAGUCAUCAGGAUGAUGAGGGAAGAUGCUACAGCGAUUCUUUAGCAGAAAUUCCUGCUGUGGAUCCCAACUUUCCUAACAAACCACCCCUUACAUUUGACAUAAUUAGGAAGAAUGUUGAAAAUAAUCGCUACCGUCGGCUUGAUUUAUUUCAAGAGCAUAUGUUUGAAGUAUUGGAACGAGCAAGAAGGAUGAAUCGGACAGAUUCAGAAAUAUAUGAAGAUGCAGUAGAACUUCAGCAGUUUUUUAUUAAAAUUCGUGAUGAACUCUGCAAAAAUGGAGAGAUUCUUCUUUCACCGGCACUCAGCUAUACCACAAAACAUUUGCAUAAUGAUGUGGAGAAAGAGAGAAAGGAAAAAUUGCCAAAAGAAAUAGAGGAAGAUAAACUAAAACGAGAAGAAGAAAAAAGAGAAGCUGAAAAGAGUGAAGAUUCCUCUGGUGCUGCAGGCCUCUCAGGCUUACAUCGCACAUACAGCCAGGACUGUAGCUUUAAAAACAGCAUGUACCAUGUUGGAGAUUACGUCUAUGUGGAACCUGCAGAGGCCAACCUACAACCACAUAUCGUCUGUAUUGAAAGACUGUGGGAGGAUUCAGCUGGUGAAAAAUGGUUGUAUGGCUGUUGGUUUUACCGACCAAAUGAAACAUUCCACCUGGCUACACGAAAAUUUCUAGAAAAAGAAGUUUUUAAGAGUGACUAUUACAACAAAGUUCCAGUUAGUAAAAUUCUAGGCAAGUGUGUGGUCAUGUUUGUCAAGGAAUACUUUAAGUUAUGCCCAGAAAACUUCCGAGAUGAGGAUGUUUUUGUCUGUGAAUCACGGUAUUCUGCCAAAACCAAAUCUUUUAAGAAAAUUAAACUGUGGACCAUGCCCAUCAGCUCAGUCAGGUUUGUCCCUCGGGAUGUGCCUCUGCCUGUGGUUCGCGUGGCCUCUGUAUUUGCAAAUGCAGAUAAAGGUGAUGAUGAGAAGAAUACAGACAACUCAGAGGACAGUCGAGCUGAAGACAAUUUUAACUUGGAAAAGGAAAAAGAAGAUGUCCCUGUGGAAAUGUCCAAUGGUGAACCAGGUUGCCACUACUUUGAGCAGCUCCAUUACAAUGACAUGUGGCUGAAGGUUGGCGACUGUGUCUUCAUCAAGUCCCAUGGCCUGGUGCGUCCUCGUGUGGGCAGAAUUGAAAAAGUAUGGGUUCGAGAUGGAGCUGCAUAUUUUUAUGGCCCCAUCUUCAUUCACCCAGAAGAAACAGAGCAUGAGCCCACAAAAAUGUUCUACAAAAAAGAAGUAUUUCUGAGUAAUCUGGAAGAAACCUGCCCCAUGACAUGUAUUCUCGGAAAGUGUGCUGUGUUGUCAUUCAAGGACUUCCUCUCCUGCAGGCCAACUGAAAUACCAGAAAAUGACAUUCUGCUUUGUGAGAGCCGCUACAAUGAGAGCGACAAGCAGAUGAAGAAAUUCAAAGGAUUGAAGAGGUUUUCACUCUCUGCUAAAGUGGUAGAUGAUGAAAUUUACUACUUCAGAAAACCAAUUGUUCCUCAGAAGGAGCCAUCACCUUUGCUGGAAAAGAAGAUCCAGUUGCUAGAAGCUAAAUUUGCCGAGUUAGAAGGUGGAGAUGAUGAUAUUGAAGAGAUGGGAGAAGAAGAUAGUGAGGUCAUUGAACCUCCUUCUCUACCUCAGCUUCAGACCCCCCUGGCCAGUGAGCUGGACCUCAUGCCCUACACACCCCCACAGUCUACCCCAAAGUCUGCCAAAGGCAGUGCAAAGAAGGAAGGCUCCAAACGGAAAAUCAACAUGAGUGGCUACAUCCUGUUCAGCAGUGAGAUGAGGGCUGUGAUUAAGGCCCAACACCCAGACUACUCUUUCGGGGAGCUCAGCCGCCUGGUGGGGACAGAAUGGAGAAAUCUUGAGACAGCCAAGAAAGCAGAAUAUGAAGAGCGGGCAGCUAAAGUUGCUGAGCAGCAGGAGAGAGAGCGAGCAGCACAGCAACAGCAGCCGAGUGCUUCUCCCCGAGCAGGCACCCCUGUGGGGGCUCUCAUGGGGGUGGUGCCACCACCAACACCAAUGGGGAUGCUCAAUCAGCAGUUGACACCUGUUGCAGGCAUGAUGGGUGGCUAUCCGCCAGGCCUUCCACCUUUGCAGGGCCCAGUUGAUGGCCUUGUUAGCAUGGGCAGCAUGCAGCCACUUCACCCUGGGGGGCCUCCACCCCACCAUCUUCCGCCAGGUGUGCCUGGCCUCCCGGGCAUCCCACCACCGGGUGUGAUGAACCAAGGAGUGGCCCCUAUGGUAGGGACUCCAGCACCAGGUGGAAGUCCAUAUGGACAACAGGUGGGAGUUUUGGGGCCUCCAGGGCAGCAGGCACCACCUCCAUAUCCCGGCCCACAUCCAGCUGGACCCCCUGUCAUACAGCAGCCAACAACACCCAUGUUUGUAGCUCCCCCACCAAAGACCCAGCGGCUUCUUCACUCAGAGGCCUACCUGAAAUACAUUGAAGGACUCAGUGCGGAGUCCAACAGCAUUAGCAAGUGGGAUCAGACACUGGCAGCUCGAAGACGCGACGUCCAUUUGUCGAAAGAACAGGAGAGCCGCCUACCCUCUCACUGGCUGAAAAGCAAAGGGGCCCACACCACCAUGGCAGAUGCCCUCUGGCGCCUUCGAGAUUUGAUGCUCCGGGACACCCUCAACAUUCGCCAAGCAUACAACCUAGAAAAUGUUUAAUCACAUCAUUACGUUUCUUUUAUAUAGAAGCAUAAAGAGUUGUGGAUCAGUAGCCAUUUUAGUUACUGGGGGUGGGGGGAAGGAACAAAGGAGGAUAAUUUUUAUUGCAUUUUACUGUACAUCACAAGGCCAUUUUUAUAUACGGACACUUUUAAUAAGCUAUUUCAAUUUGUUUGUUAUAUUAAGUUGACUUUAUCAAAUACACAAAGAUUUUUUUGCAUAUGUUUCCUUCGUUUAAAACCAGUUUCAUAAUUGGUUGUAUAUGUAGACUUGGAGUUUUAUCUUUUUACUUGUUGCCAUGGAACUGAAACCAUUAGAGGUUUUUGUCUUGGCUUGGGGUUUUUGUUUUCUUGGUUUUGGGUUUUUUUAUAUAUAUAUAUAAAAGAACAAAAUGAAAAAAAACACACACACACAAGAGUUUACAGAUUAGUUUAAAUUGAUAAUGAAAUGUGAAGUUUGUCCUAGUUUACAUCUUAGAGAGGGGAGUAUACUUGUGUUUGUUUCAUGUGCCUGAAUAUCUUAAGCCACUUUCUGCAAAAGCUGUUUCUUACAGAUGAAGUGCUUUCUUUGAAAGGUGGUUAUUUAGGUUUUAGAUGUUUAAUAGACACAGCACAUUUGCUCUAUUAACUCAGAGGCUCACUACAGAAAUAUGUAAUCAGUGCUGUGCAUCUGUCUGCAGCUAAUGUACCUCCUGGACACCAGGAGGGGAAAAAGCACUUUUUCAAUUGUGCUGAGUUAGACAUCUGUGAGUUAGACUAUGGUGUCAGUGAUUUUUGCAGAACACGUGCACAACCCUGAGGUAUGUUUAAUCUAGGCAGGUACGUUUAAGGAUAUUUUGAUCUAUUUAUAAUGAAUUCACAAUUUAUGCCUAUAAAUUUCAGAUGAUUUAAAAUUUUAAACCUGUUACAUUGAAAAACAUUGAAGUUCGUCUUGAAGAAAGCAUUAAGGUAUGCAUGGAGGUGAUUUAUUUUUAAACAUAACACCUAACCUAACAUGGGUAAGAGAGUAUGGAACUAGAUAUGAGCUGUAUAAGAAGCAUAAUUGUGAACAAGUAGAUUGAUUGCCUUCAUAUACAAGUAUGUUUUAGUAUUCCUUAUUUCCUUAUUAUCAGAUGUAUUUUUUCUUUUAAGUUUCAAUGUUGUUAUAAUUCUCAACCAGAAAUUUAAUACUUUCUAAAAUAUUUUUUAAAUUUAGCUUGUGCUUUUGAAUUACAGGAGAAGGGAAUCAUAAUUUAAUAAAACGCUUACUAGAAAGACCAUUACAGAUCCCAAACACUUGGGUUUGGUGACCCUGUCUUUCUUAUAUGACCCUACAAUAAACAUUUGAAGGCAGCAUAGGAUGGCAGACAGUAGGAACAUUGUUUCACUUGGCGGCAUGUUUUUGAAACCUGCUUUAUAGUAACUGGGUGAUUGCCAUUGUGGUAGAGCUUCCACUGCUGUUUAUAAUCUGAGAGAGUUAAUCUCAGAGGAUGCUUUUUUCCUUUUAAUCUGCUAUGAAUCAGUACCCAGAUGUUUAAUUACUGUACUUAUUAAAUCAUGAGGGCAAAAGAGUGUAGAAUGGAAAAAAGUCUCUUGUAUCUAGAUACUUUAAAUAUGGGAGGCCCUUUAACUUAAUUGCCUUUAGUCAACCACUGGAUUUGAAUUUGCAUCAAGUAUUUUAAAUAAUAUUGAAUUUAAAAAAAUGUAUUGCAGUAGUGUGUCAGUACCUUAUUGUUAAAGUGAGUCAGAUAAAUCUUCAAUUCCUGGCUAUUUGGGCAAUUGAAUCAUCAUGGACUGUAUAAUGCAAUCAGAUUAUUUUGUUUCUAGACAUCCUUGAAUUACACCAAAGAACAUGAAAUUUAGUUGUGGUUAAAUUAUUUAUUUAUUUCAUGCAUUCAUUUUAUUUCCCUUAAGGUCUGGAUGAGACUUCUUUGGGGAGCCUCUAAAAAAAUUUUUCACUGGGGGCCACGUGGGUCAUUAGAAGCCAGAGCUCUCCUCCAGGCUCCUUCCCAGUGCCUAGAGGUGCUAUAGGAAACAUAGAUCCAGCCAGGGGCUUCCCUAAAGCAGUGCAGCACCGGCCCAGGGCAUCACUAGACAGGCCCUAAUUAAGUUUUUUUUAAAAAGCCUGUGUAUUUAUUUUAGAAUCAUGUUUUUCUGUAUAUUAACUUGGGGGAUAUCGUUAAUAUUUAGGAUAUAAGAUUUGAGGUCAGCCAUCUUCAAAAAAGAAAAAAAAAUUGACUCAAGAAAGUACAAGUAAACUAUACACCUUUUUUUCAUAAGUUUUAGGAACUGUAGUAAUGUGGCUUAGAAAGUAUAAUGGCCUAAAUGUUUUCAAAAUGUAAGUUCCUGUGGAGAAGAAUUGUUUAUAUUGCAAACGGGGGGACUGAGGGGAACCUGUAGGUUUAAAACAGUAUGUUUGUCAGCCAACUGAUUUAAAAGGCCUUUAACUGUUUUGGUUGUUGUUUUUUUUUUAAGCCACUCUCCCCUUCCUAUGAGGAAGAAUUGAGAGGGGCACCUAUUUCUGUAAAAUCCCCAAAUUGGUGUUGAUGAUUUUGAGCUUGAAUGUUUUCAUACCUGAUUAAAACUUGGUUUAUUCUAAUUUCUGUAUCAUAUCAUCUGAGGUUUACGUGGUAACUAGUCUUAUAACAUGUAUGUAUCUUUUUUUUGUUGUUCAUCUAAAGCUUUUUAAUCCAAAUAAAUACAGAGUUUGCAAAGUGA